GCAGUGCAUUCGGUGGUAGUUUGGUGUCAGUCCUGUGUCUUGUCGGUCCUUCUAAACGUGUCCCCUUACGAUGCUGGCUCGCAACCACCUGGAAGUUGACUAAGGGGAGAAGGAGUCUCGUUGGAAAACGGAGGUUUGGAGGGACAACGGCCUCUCUUUUCGUUCUUGUCAGCGGAGCCUUCUUGGUCUUGGGGCUGUCCUCGCGUCCCCGGGCAUGAGGCUGGGGGUUGGGACUUGGUCGGGACGCGUCUCGCCUGGUUUGAGGGUUUUUGGGGCUCUCAGCUCGCUCAGUCCGCCUCCCUCCAUCCCACCUGUGAGGCUACUUUCUCACAAUUUAGGGUUGGGAUGUUAUUAAUCUCCCUGUACCUCCCACUGCUGUUCUUUAAAAUGGGGACUUUAGGACCAUCCUAAUGAAAUCGUUUUGGGAACUGGAAGAGGCACAAUUCUGUCUUCUCUUGAACUGCAUAACUGAGAACUCUGCAAAUUCCCCAAAGAAGGAGGAAAAAUGACCAUGUUCAAGGAGGCAGUGACCUUCAAGGAUGUGGCUGUGGUCUUCACCGAGGAGGAGCUGGGGCUGCUGGACGUUUCCCAGAGGAAGCUGUAUCGAGAUGUCAUGCUGGAGAACUUCAGAAACCUGCUAUCAGUGGGGCAUCAACUUUCCCACCGAGAUACUUUUCACUUCCAAAGAGAAGAAAAGUUUUGGAUCAUGGAGACAGCAACCCAAAGAGAAGGGAAUUCAGGAGGCAAGAUCCAAACUGAGUUGGAGUCUGUUCCAGAAACAGGACCACAUGAAGAGUGGUCUUGCCAGCAAAUCUGGGAACAAACUGCAAGUGAGUUAACUAGACCUCAAGACUCCAUAAGUAGCUCUCAGUUCUCCACACAAGGUGAUGUCCCCUCCCAGGUUGACGCAGGACUAUCUAUAAUUCACAUAGGAGAGACACCUUCUGAGCAUGGGAAGUGUAAAAAAUUCUUCAGUGAUGUCUCCAUCCUUGAUCUUCAUCAACAAUUACACUCAGGAAAGAUAUCCCAUACAUGUAAUGAGUACAGGAAGAGAUUCUGUUAUAGCUCAGCUCUUUGUCUUCAUCAGAAAGUUCACAUGGGAGAGAAACGCUAUAAGUGUGAUGUGUGUAGUAAGGCAUUUAGUCAGAACUCACAACUGCAAACUCAUCAGAGAAUCCACACUGGAGAGAAACCAUUCAAAUGUGAGCAGUGUGGGAAAAGUUUCAGCCGUAGAUCAGGAAUGUAUGUUCAUUGCAAAUUACACACAGGAGAAAAACCUCAUAUUUGUGAGGAAUGUGGGAAGGCCUUCAUUCACAAUUCCCAGCUUCGGGAACAUCAAAGAAUCCAUACUGGGGAGAAGCCAUUCAAAUGUUAUAUAUGUGGUAAGAGCUUCCAUAGUAGAUCAAAUCUUAAUAGGCAUUCCAUGGUCCACAUGCAAGAGAAAUCAUUUAGAUGUGAUACCUGUAGUAAUAGCUUUGGUCAGAGAUCAGCACUUAAUAGUCAUUGCAUGGACCACACAAAAGAGAAACUAUACAAAUGUGAAGAAUGUGGAAGGAGCUUCACUUGUAGGCAAGAUCUUUGUAAGCAUCAGAUGGACCAUACAGGAGACAAACCAUAUAAUUGUAAUGUAUGUGGGAAGGGCUUCAGGUGGUCCUCAUGUCUUUCAAGACAUCAGCGGGUCCACAAUGGAGAAACAACAUUCAAGUGCGACGGAUGUGGGAAGAGAUUUUAUAUGAAUUCACAGGGCCAUUCACAUCAGAGAGCCUAUAGAGAAGAAGAACUGUAUAAAUGUCAGAAGUGUGGGAAGGGCUACAUUAGUAAGUUUAAUCUUGACUUGCACCAGAGGGUCCACACGGGAGAGAGACCUUAUAAUUGUAAGGAAUGUGGAAAGAGCUUCAGGUGGGCCUCAGGUAUUUUGAGACAUAAGAGACUCCAUACUGGAGAAAAACCAUUCAAAUGUGAAGAGUGUGGGAAGAGGUUUACUGAGAAUUCAAAACUUCGUUUCCAUCAAAGAAUUCACACUGGAGAAAAGCCUUACAAAUGUGAGGAGUGUGGAAAGGGAUUCAGAUGGGCCUCAACUCAUCUAACCCAUCAAAGACUCCACAGCAGAGAAAAACUAUUCCAAUGUGAGGAUUGUGGGAAGAGCAGUGAGCACAGUUCAUGCCUUCAAGACCAACAAAGCGACCACAGUGGAGAAAAAACAUCCAAAUGUGAGGACUGUGGGAAGCGCUACGAGAGGCGCUUGAAUCUAGAUAUGAUUUUAUCAUUAUUUUUAAAUGAUAUAUAAUUAUUGUCCAUAUUUAUGGGUUACAGCAUAUUUCAAUACAUGUAUACAAUGUAUAAUGAUCAAAUCAGUGUUAUUAGCAUAUCCAUCACCUCCUUUAUCAUUUAUUUGUGGAUCAUUUAUCAUUUCUUUGUGCUUUGAACGUUCAAAAACUGCUGUUCUAGUUAUUUGAAAAUAAGUUAUUAUUAAUUAUAGUCACCUUUAGUGCUGUGGAACACUAGAACUUGUUCCUUUCAUCAUCUUACUGUACUUUCAUAUCUGUUAACGAAUCUUUCAUCAUCCACCCUCUCUCCUACUUUUCCCUUCUAGUAAUUGCUAUGCCAUGCUGCUUCUGCUUUUUUUUUUUUUUUUUUUUUUUUUUGAGAACAGAGUCUUCCAGGCUUGAGUGUAGUGGCAUGAUCCUUUCUCACUGCAGCCUCCACCUCCUGGGUUCAAGCGAUUCUCCUGCCUAAACCUCCUGAGUAGCAGGGAUUACAGGCACGCACCACCACGCCCAGCUAAUUUUUGUACUUUUUUUUUUUUUUUUUUGAGACAGAGUAUCGCUCUGUCGCCCAGUAUGGAGUGCAAUGGCUUGAUCUCGGCUCACUGCAACCUCUGCCUCCUGGGUUCAAACGAUUCUUCCCUGCCUUGGCCUCCCGAGUAGCUGGGACUACAGGCGCCCGCCACCACACCUGACUAAUUGUUGUAUGCGUAGUAGAGAUGGGGUUUUGCCAUAUUGGCCAACCUGGACUUGAACUCCUGACUUCAGAUGAUCCGCCCACCUCGGCCUCCCAAAGUGCUGGGAUUACAGGCGUGAGCCACCAUGCCCACCAUGCCUAAAAAUUUUUGUAUUUUUAGUGAAGAUGGGGUUUCACCACAUUGGCCAGGCUAGCCUUGAACUCCCAAACUCAAAUGGUCCACCUGCCUUGGCCUCCCAAAGUGCUGGGAUUACAGGCAUGAGCCACCGUGCCCAGCCAAUGCUAUGCUGCUUCUAUGAUGUCAACUUUUUAGCUUCCACAUAUGUGUGAAAACAUGUGGUAUUUAUCUUUCUGGGCCUGAAUUUACAUCACUCAACAUCAUGUUCUCCAAAGCUUAUCUUUAUCUUGCCAUAAAUGACAGAAUUUUAUUAUUUUUUAUGGUUAAAUAGUGUACCUUUGUGUAUGUAUGCCACAUUUUCUUUACCAUUUUCUGUUGAUGAACACUUAGAUUGGUUCCAUAUGUUAGCUAUUGCAAAUAGUACUAUAAUAAAUAUAGGAGUGCAGAUAGGAGUUCAACACACUGAUUUCCUUUCCUUUGGAUAUACAGCUAGUAGUGGGAUUGCUGGAUCACUUGAAUGCUGAUAUGCAUAAGAGGAUCUACACUGGAGAAAAACCAUGGAAGUGUGGAGAUUGUGGUACAUGCUUCAGUCAGGGCUCACAUCUUCAAAUUCAGUGUCUGUUCUGUAGAGAAACCUUAAUAAUGUGAUAUAUGUGACAGCAAAGAGUUAUAAGAUAUGAAUAUGUUAAUUUUAGUAGAUACUUCCGAAAAGUAUUUCAAACUGGUUGUACCACUAUAAACUCUGACCAUUAUUAGGCAAGAAUUGGCUUUUUUUUUUUUUUUCUUUUGAGACAGUCUUGCUCUGUCACCCAGACUGGCAUGCAGUGGAAUGAUCACGGCUCCCUGCAGCCUUGACCUCCCAGGCUCAAGAAAUCCUUCUGCCUCAGCCCCUCAAAAGCUGGGACUAUAGGCAUGCAACAACACGCCUGGCUAAAUUUUUGUUGUAGAGAUGGGGUCUCACUAUGUUGCCCAAAUUGGUCUCAAACUCCUGGGCUCAAGCGAUUCUCCCUCCUCAGCCUUCCAAAGUGCUGGGAUUACAGGCCUGAGCCAUGCGCACAGCAUUUUGUUUUGUUUUGUUUUGUUUUUGAGAUGGGGUCUCUCGGUGUUGCCCAGGCUGGAUUGCUUAUUCACAGAUGCAGUUACAGUGCCCUAUAGCCUCGAACUCCUGGGCCUAAGUGAUCCUCUUGCUUCAAUCCCCUGAGAAGCUGGGACUACAGGCAUGGACCACCACCCCUGAUUGAUCUUCUUUAGUUUCUAUAACAAAAUAGUACACUGUUUCCACAAACUUGGGAAGGCUAGUAUUUGGGGGUGGGGGGCGUGGAAAUCACUAAACAACAAAGAAAAUCUGAUGAAUUGGACAGCAUAAAAAUAUUGGCAUAAAGAUGAACAUAACAUAAGCAGGAAUAUUUAAAGCACAUACUUUUUAUAGAGUGUCUCCCCUGUAAUGUCUCUGGUUAAAUGAAAGGGUUUCAAAUGUGAAGACAACCCUAACCAUACUCAUUAUCUGUAAAAGAUGUAGCAUUGUCAUGGACUCCUUAAUAAACGUGAAGACUUUAAUCCA